AUGAGCAGCCUCCAACUUCCCUCCCUGUGCGCGCUGUGGACCGUCAGCCCUGAGCCGGGCGGGGGCUGGGGCCGUACACCUGGCGGCUGGAACGGUGAGGAAGCAGGCAGUGGGCGAGAAGAUGGAUUCCUUUUUGGACAGACAAGACCAGAGAGUGAAGCGGGAAUAACUCAUCCUCCCUACCUCCCCAGCAAGGAAACCUCUACAAACAGGAGCAGCCAAGCAGGACUGAGGCCCUUGCCCCCCAAGCAUCUUCUCAAAGAAGGGCAUGUGGGGGCCUGACAGCUCAGCUGCAUGUGUCAGCAGCUCCAGCCCCACCAUGAACAUCUGAACUCCUCAGCGGGGUAAUGGACCCCCUCCUUUCCCCCGGAGACACAGCCUGAGUGGCAGGAAUACAGAGCCUUUGGAGAGUGGCUCCCUCUCAGCUCCGUCAUGCAAGAACACUCUCUGCACCCAGCCCAUUCUGCCAAGUGACUUAAAGGAAUUAAAAAAAAAAAAAGCCUUGGUAAACAAAAAGGGGGUAAAAGCCACGCAGAGGCCCUUCAGAAGAGGUGGCGGGCUGCAGACAAAAGGGCAAGAGUUGAAAAGGGCUGUGGAGGUAGCAAGCAGCAGAGGCCACCCUGCUCAGGGCUGGGUGCCAGGCCACAGGGCAUGCCCGACGAACAGGGAGUCGGAACCCCCUCAGGCCACCCUCGGGAGUCCUGGGGUCCAGAGGGGUGUCCCUGUACCCCUUGCACACAGGACCCUCACUCUGCAGGGAUAAGCCAGCUGCGCCUGCAGCCUAGGGUGCCAAGGAGGCUGCUGAUUGUGGCCCACAGCCUCAUCUGAACGCCAGGAGACCAGGAUACCGAGGCACCGGAUCCCCUCUCUGUGCCCUGGGGAGCCCCAGUGCUGCCCAGUCACCCCAGGGCUGAGGUCUGCGUCCCUAGUGGUGCAAGGCCUGGUAGGACCACGGGGCAGGGAAUGUGAGCGCCAUCUGAGCUCACGGUGUCCUGAGUCGCGGCUUCGUGACUUUGGCAGGGGCCUCCGGACCAGUGACCCCAGUCAAACCCAGAGGGUCUUGGGCGGCAGCGACGAAGGAGGUAAGGCCCAAGGACAAGGGAAGAGGGACGCGAAUUCAGAAGGGCUCCAGGGUGGGCCCAGGGUUCCUCGCACCCAGACAGCUGGGUUGCACCCUCCAAAGGCCCCUUUUCCCAGCCAGAGCUCCACAGGUCUCCAAGGGUCUGCAGCUCCAUCCCACACACCCACUCACGCAGUUCAUGCAGCUGGCAGCUUCUGCUUGCCGGCAUAAGCAUCAUUUGCCACCUGGUGGUCCCCGUGCUGCUGGGCUCUACCCAGCAGCUGGACCCAGGAUGUAAUGGAGUGGCCUCUCCUGGAGUAAAUGGCCCUGCAGCAGGGUGGAGGAAUCUCAUUUUGAGCCCCCUCCCUAAAGGUGGUAGCAGUGAGGCCUUGGCGGGGUGGUGGGCAGGAGCUCUGGUAACCUAGGCUACUUGCCCUGGCGCCUGCUGCCCUUGAACGAGAGGGAGUCCACAAGUCUAUAUCAGGGCCCGCCCCUGUUCUGGCCAGGGGACCCAGGGUGGGUUGAUCCAAAGCUACUGCCCAAGGUCCUGCUCCUGUUGGCCCUUGGGCACCAUCUGCACUGGCUUCCAGUUCAGCCUCUUUGUUGGUUACUGGAGCAAGCUGAGGCCCAGAGAAGGGCAGAGAGUGCCCCAAGGGUCACACAACAGGCGGUGAGUCCUCCCUGCCGCUGAGGAGGGGCUGACUCCUCCAGGGAUCCCAGGAGGCCAGAGGGAGAGGCUGCACCGCCAAAAACACAAAUCCCAGCAACCUCAAGCCUCUGUGCCCUGGGCAGGACAGGGAAGCCCCAAUUCAUUACCAAGAUGGAAAAUGACACUUCCCACGCUCUUCCUCAGGAGAGGGGUUGAUUUAUGAUUGCACCAGGGCCUGGGACAUUCGUCAGCACGGCGCAGCAUGCAUGCCAUCUGCGGGGGCAUUAAUAGCCAUGUUAUUAGCCACCGGUGUGAAAGAUGCCCUGCGGAUGGGCUAUUUGCUGUUAUUUAUUAUAAAAGUGCGCCAGCCCGACAGCGGGGCCGCGAGCGUGCCUGAGCCGGAGCUGGGCUGGCUGCUUCUCUCCCAGUGCCCAGCCCUGGUCCCUACUGCCCCUCUAGUCCCUAGGAGGGCUCGGGGGUCAUUCCCAGGCUGAAGCCAAGCUAGAGGGGAGCAGCUGCUGUCCCCCAGGCCUGCUGCCAUGAAAGGUCUGCUCAGUGGCUCUGUGCAAAGGGAGGCAAGAAACAAACGCUCUGGGCAGACAGACCUGGGUUGGGGCCUGGCCCUCUGGUUGUGAGCAUGUGACCUUGGACAGGUCUGCCCCUCCCUGUAUGCCUCCCCUUUCUGCACUGGGGAUGCAGCCUGUCCCCUCCACACAGGCUGUGGCCAGCUGGAGAGAGCAUUCUAUGACGUGCCCAACACUCAGGCACCCAGCCCUGCCAGCUACUCCUAAUGCUAAGAGGCGUGACCCCACAGGCAUGAGUGACCCCACAGGCGUGAGUGACCCCACAGGCUUGAGGGGCUGCAGACAUGCUGGUGGAGAAGAGCGGCUCCCAUGAGGCCCUGCUGGAGUUGAGACACUGUUCCCCAGCAUCCUCCCUGUGCCAAACCCCUGGGAAAGGGUUACAGUUGGGCGCCAAGGCCCCAGGAGGUGGGCGGGGAGGCUGCCCACAGCUGCGGGAGGGCUCUGUCUCCACCCUGAGCCUGUCUCUUCCAUGCAGGGCCUCAGAUUUUCCUCAUCUGCAAAAAGCAGACAAUCGCUGAGGUCCUUUAUCUCAUGAUUCCAGGGUCCUGAGUGGUGGGUUCCAUCCGUGAGUGUAUCUGUGGGGUGGGCGGGAGGGGAAAAGGCCCUCUGUAGGAAAGUGAGGAUCACCUCUGAUAGUUGGAGACAGACAGGCAGUUGGGCAGUGCCAGGCCAGCAUCCAUAUCAGUGGGGGUGAGGAGGGAUGGCCAAGAGUCUCCCUUUGGGGUCAGAGAGGUCCCGCUGGGCAGCUGAGAUAGGCGGUAGGAGACCUGGGAAGGGGAGAGCUCCAGACAUCGAGUCUGAGGCCUGGGUUUGUGGCCACCCCUCUGCCAUCUGCUGCACAAUCCAGACCUUUCCCUUUGCCUCUUUGGGCUGCUGUGGUGAGGGCACCCUGGGUCACCAUGACGUCCUGGGGUGGGCUGUAGGAAGGCCAGCCUCCCUCUUCUCUACCACCCAGCCCUGGGUCUAGGUUCAGGGGCCUCCCUUUUGGUGGCCCUGUUCAUUCAUUCAUCAGAUGUUUACUGAGCACUUUCUGUGCCAGGCUCCAUGCCAGGCACAAGGCAGACCAUGUCCUAACUAUAGGAGUUUACAUUCUAAGGGGAGGAGACAAUCCAUAAACUCAUGAUAAAUAAAUAGGGAGGGUCCCACUGGGAGAAGGGCCUGCCUCCUGCCUUGUCAGGGUUGUUCUCAGCCCCUGAGAGGCCCUGCCCUCAGAGCCCAGUGCCAAGCCUCUGAUCUAGGAUCAGUGAGUGUUGCCCAUCACCAGCCUUUACUGGUCACACUGCUCCUCUCCAGGCUCUCUGCUGUGGCCCAGGAUCCUAAAGGCGGCUGAGGAGAGAAGCAGUGCAGAGCCCGCAGCCUCAGUCCUGUUCUGGAGGACUGUCCCCAGCCCUGCUGGUGCUGCCUCUCUUCCUUUUCCUCAUCCCCCAAAAUAAAGACCUUUAGCCCCUCUCCUUCCCUCUGAAAUUCCACUGGGCUUUCUUUUAUUUAUUUUAUUUUAUUUUUUUUUGAGAUAGGGUCUUACUCUGUCACUCGGGCUGGAGUGCAGUGGCACGAUCUCUCGGCUCACUGCAACCUCCGCCUCCCAGGUUCAAGUGAAUCUCCUGCCUCAGCCUCCCAAGUAGCUGGGAUUACAGGCAUGCACCACCAUGCCCAGCUAAUUUUUGUAUUUUUAGUAGAGACAGAGUUUCGCCAUGUUGACCAGGCUGGUUUUGAACUCCUGACCUCAGGUGAUCCACCUGCCUCAGCCUCCCAAAGUGCUGGGAUUACAAUGAGCCAACUUGCCCAGCCCACUGGGCUUUCUUUUUCCCUUCCAUAAAGGAAUUAAGUCUCAGUUUAGGCAGCUUUACUAAAAAUGGACACAGACAGACAGAAAUAUCAGGUGUAGGAGCAUCUUAUUAAAUAAUGCCGAGAGAGAAAGGAACAAAAUUACACGUGUCUCCUUUCAUCCCCCCACCCCCUCCUGGCCUUGAAUGGUUUAAUAUCGAACACUGUUAUCAAUAUAAUUAACUUCCUAAGACACAAUUCUAAAGUCCUGUUUUUUUAAAAGCGAUUUACAUUCUCUGAAGUUCAGGACAUCCCGCCGCCUGGCACCAGCGCCACCCAGCCGGCCUAUGUGGUUAGGUGCAUUUAUAGUGGAUUUGCAUACCUGUCUGCAAUUACCGCCAGUGAUAACAGCUGAUGCAUAAUGCAUGCAGCAUGAAAUUAGAAAAAUAAUUAACUUUAGGUUUUAAAAGAAUUCCCGCCCCAGCCCCCAUGCAUCACAAGUUCUAAAUGAUACCAGUGGAUGGGAUCCAGGAGCAAAGCUGUUCAGGGUGAUGGGUGUGGCUGGCUGGCACCCUGCCCUGGCGGGAGCUGGGGUUAGAAGGUCCUUGAGGGUCAUGGCAUCUAGUCCCUGCCCUAAGGAGAUGCCUCUGGUGGGCCUGCAGUCCCUGGGGCAUCUGCCUGAACUAGGGCUUGGAAAAGCCCCACUCACACGACUCAAGGCUCCCCUCCCUUCCUGCAGUUCAUGUCUGGGGCUCAGGGAAGAAUGGCUCAUUGCUAGUAAUGGUAAUAGUUCCCUCAUUCUGAAUACGACUCUGCUAAACAUUGAAAGUAACCUUAUUUUAUCUUCACAAAAGCCCAGGGAAGUAGAUCGUUUAUGGUCAGAUAGACUUGAGACCCCUGUAAUCCCAGCACUUUGGGAGGCCGAGGCGGGCAGAUCACCUGAGGUCAGGAGUUAGUGACCAGCCUGACCAACAUGGAGAAAUCCCGUCUCUACUAAAAAUACAAAAUUAGUGGGGCGUGGUGGUGCAUGCCUGUAAUCACAGCUACGCGGGAGGCUGAGGCAGAAGAAUCGCCUGAACCCAGGAGGCAGAGGUUGCGGUGAGCCAAGAUCGUACCAUUGCACUCCAGCCUGGGCAACAAGAGCGAAACUCUGUCUCAAAAAAAAAAAAAAAAGACUUGAGACCCAGGGCCACCCCACAGUAGGCUGAGCAGCUUGGUUGAGCCAGGCAGACCACUGGCUACUUGCCUUCACAGGAAAGGGGCUUCCUGGCGAGAAGGAGGGGAGCUCUCCCUGGGUCUCCCUGAGCACCAGGAAGCAGCGGCCUGCCCUGUCUACCUCCUGGCCCUCUUCCCUCUGUCUUAUUUGCAGUUGAGCCCCCAGGAAGGUGGGGUCUUUCAUUAAUUUAAACAAAGGUUUGCUGAAGCCCCAUCACAGAGCUGGAGAUGAUUGUGCCUUGGUAGGGCUUCCUGUCUAGUGGGAGGUGGGACUGGGGUCCCACUGGCCUUUCCCGCUCUGGGGCUGAGAAACUGCUUCUGCCCGCAGUCUGCCUGCACGGCAUUCUCAGUGAGGAAUUGAAGGCAUGGCAAGGUUUAGGGGAGACACAUGAAUUAUUGCUGAAGGGAGGGACUGGCAGGGGAAAGACACCUGCAAGGGACCCCACCUGGGGGCUGGGAAGUGGGGGAAAAGCCAAAGGACCCCAGGGUCUGCAGCAACCACACACCAGUGCCAGGCCACACACCAGUGCCAGGCCACAUGGGCAGCCAGAUUCCUAAGGACAGAGGCAGGCAGGUGGGCAGGAAGGAGGCUGAGGGGCAAGUGGGGGUGGGGGAGACGUGACCAGCAUCCAUGCACGUGAGCAUGUACUUGUCUUUCCUACAUACAGAGUUUACAUGCAGGACACUUCCUCUCCCCGCCUGGCCCUGCCUGAGAUGCCCCCAUCCCAGGGAUGGGACAGGUGAAAGAGGAGACGUGGGAGUGAGGCCAGACAGGGAUGGGGGGCUAUUUCCUUGCUGGCUUCCAGAAGCUCCUGGGACAUGCCUGUGAAUAGAAAAUAGCAUCCCCAGGUUCCAUGAGGGCCAGGAGCCAGCAGCAGGGUCCCCAGCAAAGGCUGAGCAGCAGACAGUGGGCCAUAAGCCACCACGAGGGGUGGGGAAGAAGCUUGGUGUCACUGACUUAUAAAGGCUUUGCAGUUGGGUGUAGACACCCACACUCAGCUUCCCUACUGCUCCCCCAGACCUGGGAAACCCGGGAGGCUGCCGGCCUCUCCCCACUCGUGACACUGGGCAGCAGCUCCACAAAGGGUCUAAUGCACCGUGAGCACAGCUUCUGGGGAGGGCUGCAGAGGGGGUGGAAAGGGGAGGGACAGAAGCCUCAGGACUUCUCAGGGGUGGGAGUGAGUGUGGCGUGGAGGAGGUAGGGAACUAUUUCUGGCCACUGGAUGACCUGGUGACGAAGGCCCAUUUAAAACCCUCUUACCUCCCCGGACUCCUCCACCCUGCCCCCAGCCUGGAGGGCCUCCCAUGGGAGGCUGGUGCGGCCCCACAGGAGGGGAUGGUUGAUGGCCCCAUCCACCAGCUCUGUGCGGCCCAGACAUAGGGUCAAGGCUGCCAGCAUGGCUUGGGGGAGGGGCAGGGUUGCACCCACACAGUUUGAGGUGGGCAGGGGGCAACACCUCAGCUUCACAGAGGCUGAUAAGGGGUCAGCCUGUCCGGAAGGCACAGCAGGAGCAGGGGAGUAGAGAACGGGCCACUGGAGCGCGGAGGACAGAGACGGGCAGCUACUGCAGAAGCUAGGCCGUGUGUCUGGGGAGGCAGAGACUUGGGGCAGCUUUUAAACUGGAUGCGUCGGGGGCAUCCAGAUCACACUCAGGAGGGGGUACUCUGCACAUAUAAUGUCAGUGAAUCCUGAAUUGUAAGUUCCCAUGUAAGGGCCCCUAUUAUGACCACAUUUAUAGAUGAGGAAAUCAAACCUCAGAGAGGGCAAGCAGCUUGCUCAAAAUAACACAGCCUGAGGCCCGGCGUGGUGGCUCACGCGUAUAAUCUCAGCACUUUGGGAUGCUGAAGUGGGCAGAUUGCUUGAGCCUAGGAGUUCAAGACCAGCCUGGGCAACAUAGCAAAACCCCAUCUCUGCAAAAAAUACAAAAAUUAGCUGGGUGUGGUGGUGCAGCAUGUGGUCCCAGCUCUGCAGGAGGCUGAGGUGGGAGGAUCACCUGAGCAUGGGGAGGUCGAGGCUGCAGUGAGCCGUGAUCGGGCCACUGCAUUCCAGACUGGGUGACAGAGCGAGACUGUCUCAGAAAAAAAAAAAAAAGAAAGAAAUCAUACCACCUGAAAGUGGCAGAGGCAGGAUUUGAACCCAGGCCUCUCUGUCCUGGAGGUUGGCAGGGGACAACGACUGAUAGAGCCAAGAAUAAUGCCAAGAAUAAUGCCCCAGGGCCCCCAGCUAAGCGGAGGAGUAAUGGACACCUACAGCCUGAGCCAUCCCACUGCUCCCUUCGCCCACCCCCGUGGCCCGCUAAGGAUCCGGCUGUCAGUCAUGGAGCUGGCAGGUCGUAACUCACACCACGCUGAAGUCUGAGGGAUCCACGCAAGGGCGACAAGCGAUCCCAUAAAAGAUGGGCGAUUUACCAGGUUUAAUUUGAUGGCCACAUAAACUAUGAAACACACAACAAGGGAAUAAAAAGGCAAGCAGGCACCCAGGCAAUUAGAGAUUCCUCUGGUGAGGCGUGCUAUCUUCCUCCCCACCCCCAGGUCCCGCCCUACUUUCCUGGAGCCAGAGGGCUCAGCCUCGGGCUGGCCUUGGGGAGGGGGGCGGCAGGGGAGCCUUUGGCCAAGAUGGAUGAGGCCCACAGACAGUGGAGCGGAAAGGCCUUGGGUCCCUGCCUCCCAAAUGCUUCUUGGUUAUCCAUCAAGCAUCUCUGAAAGGUGCAAUUUAGACUCUAUUAUGAUGCUGAGGCCUCUGAAGGCUGAGGACUGUGGCCAUGAGCUGAGCGGGCGCUGGGAACAGAUGUCCAUACCAGGGAAUGCGGUGGCUUGCCUUGGCUUUGGCCUUAACAAGUUUGCCCCCUACUUAGGGCACUGCUCAGAACAGCUGAGUACAAAGGCCACCUGUAUCCCUUGUGCCAGAACUCAGCAGCCAACAGACCAGGUUGGGGGUAAUCCUCCAGCCAGACGCUGGGGGCCCCCUGGCAGAGGUGCUCCUAGACUCAGACUUGACCCUGGAGACUGAGGCAAAGUGACCUGUGAGCUGGCCUGUGUCUUCCUGUCUCUAGCAUUGCCCUGUGCUACCUACCUGCUCAUAAGUGGCUUGAGGCAGGACCUCCGGCUCCAUAACCUUCACGAGCCUGGCUCAGUGCAGAAGGGACAGACGUGCAGUGGGAAAUCUGGGCUGGCUGUGACCUUGGCUGGGCCCCUCAUGUCUCUGAGUCUCAGGCUGCUGGGCUGUGAAAUGAGGGCUGUGGACCUGUGUGUAGGCGGCAACCUCUGCACCCUUGCCUGUGAAGGGGGGUGGGUGAGGUCUGGCCAGAGAGGUCACCCCACCACCUAGGCUUUUCCUGAUCCUCUGAAGGCUGAUGUGUCUAGCUCUGCAUGCUGUCCUGGCUUCAAGCCCGUCCUUUCCCAUGAUCUGGGCCAGUGUCCUUCCCAGUCCCCAAUGUAAUGAAAGGUGAGGUGGUCAGAUAAGGGUCAGAGCAGCCUGGGAUGGCCCUGGGCAAAGGAAGCAGGAGGCUCACAGGAGAGUGGGCAUCUCCAUGAAGGUCUGAGAAUGCUCAGCCUGGGCUGCAGGACUGUGUCUGGGCUGGCCAGGGACUCACAGCCCUCAGCAGUGUGGAGUCAAGCACUGAGGUCCUGCAGCCACGCAGCCCUGGGGUGGAAUCCAGACCCCACCUCCUUCUGCCAGGGGACCAUGGACAGGUCUCUGUGCCUCUGUUCUCUCAUCUACAGAACGAGUCCAUCACAGUUUCUCCUUUGAAAUCUUUAGUGAGCAUCUGCCACGUGGGAAACACUAUGAAUAAGAUGCACAAAUCCCUGCCCUUGUAGAGCGUACCUUCUAGUGGGGAGACAGACAAUAAAAACAAAAAAGGGCCAGGCACUGUGGCUCACCUGUAAUCCCAGUACUUUGAGAGGCCCAGGGAGGUGGAUCACGAGGUCAAGAGAUCAAGACCAUCCUGGCCAACAUGGUGAGACCCCCGUCUCUACUAAAAAUACAAAAAAUUAGCUGGGCAUGGUGGUGCACACCUGUAGUCCCAGCUACUCAGGAGGCUGAAGCAGGAGGAUCUCUUGAACCUGGGAGGCGGAGGUUGUAGUGACCCAAGAUCGCUCCACUGCACUCCCACCUGGUGACAGGGCAAGACUCCAUCUCAAAAAGCAAAACAAGGCAAAACAAAACAAAAAAGAUAAAACACGUAGUGUGUUAGUUGGUGGUAAAUACUAUAGGCAAGCAAGGAACUGAGAGGAGUAUCUGGGAGUUAUAAUUCUCGAUAGGGUGCCCAGGAAAGGCCUCACUGGAAGGAGAUGCAGGCGUGGAUCUGGGGAUGAGCUGUCCAGGCAGAGAGCACAGCACUUGCAAGGGCCCUGGGGAUACUAGGGGGUGCCUGGCUGCUGCAGUCAGUGAGAGGGGAAUGGGGUGGACCAGGCCAACAGGGGUGCCACAUAGGAUUGCACAGGGCCUUAGCAGCCACCUUGAUGACUGUGGUGGCUGCCUGGGCAGAGACCCUGUAAGUGUGAAGGGAACGUUUGAGUGUGCAGGGGUGAGUGGCAGAGACAUUCACCACGGCAGGGCCCAUUCUGUCAUCGGGUGGUCACUGAUGCAAAGCCAUGCUUGGCCACAGUCCCUGCCCUGGCAGUUUGGUGACAUGAAAACACCAGUCACCAAAUGGUGUGACCUGCAACCCACAGAGUGCUGCAAGCCUCAAGAUUGCCAAGAUUCUGGCCUCCUCCCUAGAUGGCCUGGGUUCCUCCUACCUGGUUCUCAAGUAGUCUUGAGUAAGCUAACAUCUCUGAGCUUCAAUUUUCUCAUCUGUUAAAUGGGAUUAAGGGCACUGACCUCAUGUUUGUUGGGAGGGUUAAAUGACUUAAAUAUUAGGAAAGUUCUCAGCAAAGCCUUUAUUAUAGUGUGAACUAUCAUCCAUCCCAUCAGAAUGGAAUCCCAAGUGGCUACAACAGGGCCUGGAAUAUAGUAGAUGCUCAAUAAAGCUCUGUUGGAUGCAUGAUGGAUGGAUGGAUGGAUGGAUGGACAGGUGCAUGUGUGAAUGGACAGGUUGAUGCAUGGAUGGAUGGAUGGAUGGAUGGAUGGAUGGACAGGUGGAUGCAUGGAUUGAUGCAUAUAUGGAUGGAUGGAUGGAUGGUUGGAUGGAUGGAUAAUUGGAUGGAUGGAUAGACAGGUGGAUGCAUGGAUGGAUGGAUGGAUGGACAGGUGGAUGCAUGGAUAGCAUGGAUGGAUGGAUGGUUAGGUGGAUGGAUGGAUGGAUGGAUGGAUGGAUGGAUGGAUGGAUGGAUGGGCAGACAGGUGGAUGCAUGGAUGGAUGGAUGGAUGGUUAGGUGGAUGGAUGGACGGACAGGUGGAUGCAUGGAUUGAUACAUGGAUGAUGGAUGGAUGGAUGGACGGACAGGUAAAUGCAUGAUGGAUGGAUGGACAGGUGCAUGCAUGAUGGAUGAAUGAACAGGUGGACGCAUGGAUGGAUGGAUGGAUGGAUGGACAGCUGGAUGUAUGGAUUGAUACAUGGAUGGAUGGAUGGAUGGAUGGAUGGAUGGAUGGAUGGACAGGUGGAUGCAUGGAUUGAUGCACGGAUGGAUGGAUGGAUGGAUGGAUGGAUAAUUGGAUGGAUGGAUAAUUGGAUGGAUGAAUGGACAGGUGGAUGCAUGGAUGGAUGGAUGGAUGGACAGGUGGAUGCAUGGGUUGAUGCAUGGAUGGAUGGAUGGAUGGAUGGAUGGAUGGAUGGAUGGACAGGUGGAUGCAUGGAUGGAUGCAAGGACUGGUGCAUGCCUGAAUGGAUGAAUGAACAAGUGGAUGGAUGCAUGGAUGCCUGGAUGGAUGGAUGGUUAGAUGGAUGGAUGGAUGGAUGGAUGAAUGGACAGAUGGAUGCAUGGAUGAAUGGAUGGUUAGGUGGAUGGAUGGAUGGAUGGAUGGAUGGACAGGUGGAUGCAUGGAUUGAUACAUGGAUGACGGAUGGAUGGACGGACAGUAGAUACAUGAUGGAUGGAUGGAUGGACAGGUGCAUGUAUGAAUGGAUGGAUGGGUGAAUGGACAGGUGGAUGCAUGGAUGGAUGGAGGGAUGGUUGAAUGGAUGGAUGGAUGGAUGAAUGGAUGGAUAGAUGGAUGGAUGGAGGGAUGGUUGAAUGGAUGGAUGGAUGGAUGAAUGGAUGGAUGGAUGGACAGGUGGAUGUAUGGAUUGAUGCAUGGAUGGAUGGAUGGAUGGAUGGACAGGUAGAUGCAUGAUGGAAGGAUGGUGGACAGAUGGAUGGAUGGAUGGACAGGUGCAUGCAUGAAUGGAUGGAUGGAUGAAUGGACAGGUGGAUAGAUGGAUGGAUGGACAGGUAGAUGCAUGGACUGAUACAUAGAUGGAUGGAUGGAUGAAUGGAUGGAUGGAUGGACAGGUCCAUGCAUGAAUUGAUGGAUGGAUGAAUGUACAGGUGGAUGGAUGGUAGGUGGGUGGACAGAUGGAUGGGCAGAGCAGAGGGAAGCUUUAUCUGGGGCCUCAGGAAAACCUAGCAGAGGAGGUAACAUUUGAGCUGGGUCCUGCAAGAGUAGCUUGCUCGAUGGAAAGAAAAAGCAGCUCAGGAAUAGAGAAGGACAGAGAAGACAGAAAGUUUGGCCUGGUUGAGUAACAGAGAUGUUCAGUCCCUGGGGCAUGAAAAUAAGGUCCCUGCUGGCUCAGUGAGCAGGUGCCGGCUCUGCUCUGCACACCAGGGCUGCCCUCCCAGGCUGGGACUUCAGGUUCCGAGAGGCCAUCAUGUCCCAUCAUUGAAAAGCCUCCGUGAACCCAGUGUUUUACAGCAGACUUUUGCUGGCUGCAUGAAGACACCUUCCUCACUGAGACUGAAAGAUAAUUUCUCUUUAAUUGAUUUUUUACCACUAUGAACAGUAAAAUAAUAUAAGAAAAAUCUAUGCUGCUAUUUUUCCAUUUGUGAAAUCCAAAAUUACACCUUGCAGCCAAUUCCCUCAGAGUACAGACGUGACUCCUCCCUCCUUUUAUUUGUCUCAUUCCUUUAAGUGCAAGAAAACAGACCACUUUUUUUUUUUUUGAAUAGCUGAAAGUUUAUGAUUUGAGAAAGGGGCAAGGUGUGGGACAAUUUCCCACACAACUCGGAACCCAGGGCCAGGGAGGCACCUCUGAUGAAAAGAGAUUUCUGUAAAUACAUGAGAAAGUGAUUCUGUUGACACCUCAUUCUUCUGUCUGUAGAAUGUACGAGUGACAACAGGACAUGUUGUUUUAACACCAGACAAUGAAGCUCCCUGCUCUCCACUCCUCGCCAGUGAUGGCACUGACAGCUUCGUUCCCGCAGGUUCUGGCGACGCCCCCCUUUUGAGCUCCUGGGCCUUCCAGCAACAAGCUUUCCUUUCGAAUCCUGGGUCCGAGCCAGACAGCAAUGCGUGCUCCUCGUGCAGUGCCAGGGAAACAGCAGCUAUGAAUCCAUAAAACACGCCCUAAAUCCAUCCCAUCCAUAUUGACUGGUACCUUUAGCGUUGGCCAUAAAGUGGCUUUGUGUGAAGUCUUGAGAGAAGAAACCAAGCCUGCUGCAUGGCUCUCACUAAAUUAACCUCCCUGAGGCUCCGGAUCACAUUCCAGGAGGGCCGCGGCAGCACGGGUCUCAUUAAUGCGCAGCCUCUUGGCUCCUGAUAAGAUUUAACAUUAGCCAGAUGUUGUUAGAGUCCGACCUCGGCGGGAGCAAUCACCUGCGGCAUAAACCUGGCACAAAGGCCACUCCUCCAGCUUGACCUCACCCCGCAGGACCGGACUUCGGUCACCCCUUGGUAUUCAGGCUCCAGGCCAGGUGGGGCCGGACGCCCCCAGCCAUCCACCAUGGUGGUGGCACACCCCACCGCCACUGCCACCACCACGCCCACUGCCACUGUCACGGCCACCGUUGUGAUGACCACGGCCACCAUGGACCUGCGGGACUGGCUGUUCCUCUGCUACGGGCUCAUCGCCUUCCUGACGGAGGUCAUCGACAGCACCACCUGCCCCUCGGUGUGCCGCUGCGACAACGGCUUCAUCUACUGCAACGACCGGGGACUCACAUCCAUCCCCGCAGAUAUCCCUGAUGAUGCCACCACCCUCUACCUGCAGAACAACCAGAUCAACAACGCCGGCAUCCCCCAGGACCUCAAGACCAAGGUCAACGUGCAGGUCAUCUACCUAUACGAGAAUGACCUGGAUGAGUUCCCCAUCAACCUGCCCCGCUCCCUCCGGGAGCUGCACCUGCAGGACAACAAUGUGCGCACCAUUGCCAGGGACUCGCUGGCCCGCAUCCCGCUGCUGGAGAAGCUGCACCUGGAUGACAACUCCGUGUCCACCGUCAGCAUUGAGGAGGACGCCUUCGCCGACAGCAAACAGCUCAAGCUGCUCUUCCUGAGCCGGAACCACCUGAGCAGCAUCCCCUCGGGGCUGCCGCACACGCUGGAGGAGCUGCGGCUGGAUGACAACCGCAUCUCCACCAUCCCGCUGCAUGCCUUCAAGGGCCUCAACAGCCUGCGGCGCCUGGUGCUGGACGGUAACCUGCUGGCCAACCAGCGCAUCGCCGACGACACCUUCAGCCGCCUACAGAACCUCACAGAGCUCUCGCUGGUGCGCAAUUCGCUGGCCGCGCCACCCCUCAACCUGCCCAGCGCCCACCUGCAGAAGCUCUACCUGCAGGACAAUGCCAUCAGCCACAUCCCCUACAACACGCUGGCCAAGAUGCGUGAGCUGGAGCGGCUGGACCUGUCCAACAACAACCUGACCACGCUGCCCCGCGGCCUGUUCGACGACCUGGGGAACCUGGCCCAGCUGCUGCUCAGGAACAACCCUUGGUUUUGUGGCUGCAACCUCAUGUGGCUGCGGGACUGGGUGAAGGCACGGGCGGCCGUGGUCAACGUGCGGGGCCUCAUGUGCCAGGGCCCUGAGAAGGUCCGGGGCAUGGCCAUCAAGGACAUUACCAGCGAGAUGGACGAGUGUUUUGAGACGGGGCCGCAGGGCGGCGUGGCCAAUGCGGCUGCCAAGACCACGGCCAGCAACCACGCCUCUGCCACCACGCCCCAGGGUUCCCUGUUUACCCUCAAGGCCAAAAGGCCAGGGCUGCGCCUCCCCGACUCCAACAUUGACUACCCCAUGGCCACGGGUGAUGGCGCCAAGACCCUGGCCAUCCACGUGAAGGCCCUGACGGCAGACUCCAUCCGCAUCACGUGGAAGGCCACGCUCCCCGCCUCCUCUUUCCGGCUCAGUUGGCUGCGCCUGGGCCACAGCCCAGCCGUGGGCUCCAUCACGGAGACCUUGGUGCAGGGGGACAAGACAGAGUACCUGCUGACAGCCCUGGAGCCCAAGUCCACCUACAUCAUCUGCAUGGUCACCAUGGAGACCAGCAAUGCCUACGUAGCUGAUGAGACACCCGUGUGUGCCAAGGCAGAGACAGCCGACAGCUAUGGCCCUACCACCACACUCAACCAGGAGCAGAACGCUGGCCCCAUGGCGAGCCUGCCCCUGGCGGGCAUCAUCGGCGGGGCAGUGGCUCUGGUCUUCCUCUUCCUGGUCCUGGGGGCCAUCUGCUGGUACGUGCACCAGGCUGGCGAGCUGCUGACCCGGGAGAGGGCCUACAACCGGGGCAGCAGGAAAAAGGAUGACUAUAUGGAGUCAGGGACCAAGAAGGAUAACUCCAUCCUGGAAAUCCGCGGCCCUGGGCUGCAGAUGCUGCCCAUCAACCCGUACCGCGCCAAAGAAGAGUACGUGGUCCACACUAUCUUCCCCUCCAACGGCAGCAGCCUCUGCAAGGCCACACACACCAUUGGCUACGGCACCACGCGGGGCUACCGGGACGGCGGCAUCCCCGACAUAGACUACUCCUACACAUGAUGCCCGCCCACCCGGGCUGCCCCGCCUCAGCCCCAGCUGCCCUGGCGUGGCCAUGUGGCUUUGCCCAGCCUGCUGCAAUCCAAGAGAGCAAGGAAGAGAAAUUCCAUGGGUGACUUUCCUCCGCAGAAAGCAAAGUUUGGGGAGGGCUGACGAUUUUGUAGAACACAACAGUGACAAUUUUUUUUAAAAGAAUAGAAGGCAGGAGGGGGAAUUCGACAUUGUUGAAGACAUAAUUUAUACCAAGUUAUGCCAGUUGGGGAGGGAAGGACUAAAAAUAAUAUUGCAGGCAGGGCUGGGUUGGGUUUUUUUUUUUUCCCCCCUGAACUGGAAGGAUACUACCUGUACAACAUCUGUGGACACCUCAUGCUCUGUUCAAGGCCAUCACAAAGGAACCGCCAGGGAGAAGCAGCCGGCUCUCAAAGCUCCCACGCAGCUCUCCCGCCACUGGCCACUCGCUGGCGACCCGAUGGAAGGUUUUCAGGCUCCUCACAAAGGAGAGAGGGAAGAAAAGAUCUUUUGCCCUGGAGAUAUGGUCCUGAAAUCUCUCCCCUGGCUUAUUCCAUACCAUUUCCCUUGCAGAUUUGCAGAAACAUGGCAUCUUUCACUGCAUUCUUUGAACAAUCAUGUAGUCGAUUAAAAAAAAAAAACAAACUUUUUUUUCCUAGGCUGAAGCCCUCUUCAGUUCCAUGCACCACGCUCCGUAGAAGCCCCGGCGGAAGCCGUAGCUUUCCCUGCCACCUGGAGGUGCAUCUGUCUGCCUGUCUAUCCCUGUCGCGGUGUCUCUAAGUACAGAUGGGUAGAUAGAGCCACAUGCACGGUCCUUACCGUUCUUCUUGGGUCAGUUCUUACCAUUUCCUGAACAAUAGAAUUGUGAAAGUG